UGCUGGGAUUCAUGAAAUCCAAGCAUUCCGGGACUAUAAUGAAAGAUGUUGUCUCAGAGGUGUGCUCUGUGGCUGUCGGUGUUUGUUAAUUGUGCAUCCUGCUGGGGUUAAGAACAGAAAUAGAAAAAACCAAUUGUCCUGUCUCUCCUUCCCCAAGGAGAUGAGCAUGCAGGAGGUUUCAUGGCCCAGCUCCUCCAGUGAUCACUCAGCUGUCAACCAGGCUGAGCACAUCAGAGAAUAACACCUCCUUUUCUGAGGAUUCUGAUACAUUUUCAAUCAGAAACAGAAGCAAAGAUUCUGCAGCUCCCACAGAAACUCCCAGAAACCUUCAGGGAAAUGGGGGAAAAUCAGACAAUGGUCACAGAGUUCCUCCUACUGGGAUUUCUCCUGGGCCCAAGGAUUCAGAUGCUCCUCUUUGGGCUCUUCUCCCUGUUCUAUAUCUUCACCCUGCUGGGGAACGGGGCCAUCCUGGGGCUCAUCUCACUGGACUCCAGACUCCACACCCCCAUGUACUUCUUCCUCUCACACCUGGCUGUCGUCGACAUCGCCUACACCCGCAACACGGUGCCCCAGAUGCUGGCGAACCUCCUGCAUCCAGCCAAGCCCAUCUCCUUUGCUGGCUGCAUGACGCAGACCUUUCUCUGUUUGAGUUUUGGACACAGCGAAUGUCUCCUGCUGGUGCUGAUGUCCUACGAUCGUUACGUGGCCAUCUGCCACCCUCUCCGAUACUCCGUCAUCAUGACCUGGAGAGUCUGCAUCACCCUGGCCGUCACUUCCUGGACGUGUGGCUCCCUCCUGGCUCUGGCCCAUGUGGUUCUCAUCCUAAGACUGCCCUUCUCUGGGCCUCAUGAAAUCAACCACUUCUUCUGUGAAAUCCUGUCUGUCCUCAGGCUGGCCUGUGCUGACACCUGGCUCAACCAGGUGGUCAUCUUUGCAGCCUGCGUGUUCUUCCUGGUGGGGCCACCCAGCCUGGUGCUUGUCUCCUACUCGCACAUCCUGGCGGCCAUCCUGAGGAUCCAGUCUGGGGAGGGCCGCAGAAAGGCCUUCUCCACCUGCUCCUCCCACCUCUGCGUGGUGGGACUCUUCUUUGGCAGUGCCAUCAUCAUGUACAUGGCCCCCAAGUCCCGCCAUCCUGAGGAGCAGCAAAAGGUCUUUUUUCUAUUUUACAGUUUUUUCAACCCAACACUUAACCCCCUGAUUUACAGCCUGAGGAACGGAGAGGUCAAGGGUGCCCUGAGGAGAGCACUGGGCAAGGAAAGUCAUUCCUAACUGGUGUGACAUUUGACUCUCCCUCCUCAGUCAUCUCCUGGAAUCUUGGUACCAAAUACCACCUAAGUUCACUACUCUCUUUAUAUCUGAGACUGAAUGAACCAAGAGACUCUGCAAAGCAUUCCUUUUUCCUGCCUGGGAAGUAUUUAGUUUUUGAUGCAUUUGUUAUACUUAACAUUUUUUAAUUUAAGCACUUAUUGAGUUGAGAAUGUCGGGGAAAGAUUUAUUUUGUACACUGCUAUGAGUCCAGAAGUUUAAAACAGACACUCCACCUGUGACUUAGUCAGGUAUGCUCAGUAGUAGAGGAAUAGCAGUUAUUACCAGAUAAAGUCAUAUCUAUAAAAAGUUUUUAAAAAUACAGCCACAGGCAGAGACUCCAGAACCCAUUGAUACCUCUGUCCAUUUUCAUCCUCAUUUGGAUGUUUCCCCUCAAUUGUACUUCCUUUCUUAUAAGCAGUAAAUGUACCUAAGUGCCUACUUCAGCUUGGAGGGAAAUUGAUUUUUAUAAAAUCCUACAAACUGACAAUUUCUGUUGUCAGAGAGAGUGAAUCCAUAAACAUUCAGCUGGCAAUCUGAAGCAAUUACACAACAAAAUCCACUUUCCAACCUGCCCUGAGACUGUGAUGGUCACUUGUUUCUACUCUUCUCACCUCCUCCAGGGGACUGUCUAUGAUUGUCUCUAAAUAAGCACAUGCUCUUCACUUAGAGGAAGUUAGUACCACCACACAACUUUUCACUGCUGGGGACGAAUGGAAAGCCCCACACAGAGACAAUUCAAUGGAAAAAAGCGUUUUAAUAAUAAUGUUAAUAGUUAGCAUUAUUAUAAAUUACUCUGCACCAUCCACUGCACAUUGAUAGGUACUUUAUAGAGAUAACCUCAGUUUAUCAUUAUAGCCAAUUCAUUUCCCAUUAUUAUCCCAUUUUAUAGAUGUGAACUUCAAGCAGAUGGUAAAUGUUAGACUCAUACCCAAACAAUCUGGCUCCCAAGCCUUCUUUACUUAACCAGGACAAUGUGGGACUUUAUUAGCAACAUUUCAAAUUAAGAAUAAGUCUAACCAAUCCUAACGUAGGAUAUGUUAAGUGAAUGUGGGUUUCUUCCCCAUCUAGAAUGUGCCAUGAUGAGGCCAGGAGAGUCAGAGAUUAUUUAUGGAAGGCUUCUUAUCCUGUUUGACGAGUCCUGUGGGCAUGGCUGCAAAGGAGGUUAAGAGAUUCAGAGGAACACAGAACACAGACAGGGUGGGAGUAGAGGCUGUUCUCAAUGAGAUUAGAGAGUAAGUUUAGAACUAUACUUGGUUCUGGGUGGUAAGAUCCAGAACAAAGACAUCUCUAGUUCACAUACAACACUCACAUGCUCACGUACAUGCGUGUGCACACACACACACACACACACACAUAUACGCACAGUGCUUAGUGAAGCACUAUUCCAAGAACCUUACAAGUAAGAGCUCUUUAAGUCCUCAUAAAAACCCUAUGAGGUAGAGACUAUUACUACUAUUUUUAGGCGAGAAAACAGAACUAUAGAGAGAUUAUAUAAUUUAACCAAUGCUCCCAGCUAAUAAGUACCUAGUCCAGAAUCAAACUUAGGCAAUAUGACUGCUGAACCCAUAAUCGUAACCAUUAUAUAAAAAUCAAAGAGAUCAUGAAAUUUCCAAAGAUGAAGAGGAGGAGAGAUGAAAAGCAAUUUUCAAUCUCUAGCCAAAGAUAGGCAUUGGGCUCCAGACAGAAAAGUACUUAAAGCUGGGGGAAAAACAAACAAACAAACAAACAAACAAACAAAAAACAGCUUUUUUUAUACUGGUGCGUGAAAUGAGAUGAGGUGGUAGCAAGAAGGAACUGUGACUCCAAGGGUCAGAGACGGAGGAGGAGCCUCUUGACGGGCAGGAUGGUGAAACCAAAAACAAUGGAUAAAACUUUUAAGUUGAUGGUUCAUCAAUUGAAGAACAUUAGAAAGUGUUUUUGUAAAUUAUCUAGCCGGGCAUGGCAACGUGUGCCUAUAUCCCCAGCUAUUCGGGAGGCUGAGGCAAGAGGAUCACUUGAGCCAGGGAUUUUGAGGCUGCAGUGAGCCAUGAUCGCACCACUGCAUUCCAGCCUGGGUGACAGAGUGAGACCUUGUGUCCAACAAUAAUAAAAAUGAAAUAAUUUAUUAAAUUUUUUAAAAUUACCCAAACUGGAUAUACAAUUUGUAAUUCCAUUGCUGCCGAACAGUUUUUAAACGGUUGUUUAGUUUCACGGCAGAUGCUGCAUACUGCAUUGCAACUAACACUGGGAAGGGAUACAUUCAAGUGGCAGGACAAAGGUGAGGAGCUCUAAUACCAGGGGUAGGUUUCAAGGGAUGAAUACUCCCCUGGUACCAGAGGAGCAGCAGGAAAUCAUGGUGUGCAGAAACCAUGCUCAGGCGGUUGCCUGUGUGGACCCUAAAUUCUGUGUGUGCAGUCCUCUCUUAGGAUUGGCCCAGGCAUCCAAGAAGCCCACGAUGCUGCCUACCCCUUAAAUACACAAGGUGCGUACCGGAGGCCCUGGUUCUAGUUCCAGAUGUACCAUUUGCUAGCUGUGUUUUUUGCAGAGAAGUCCCUUAAACUGCUUAAGCUUCAGUCCUUCAUCUGAAAAUUAUGCAUAUGGAAGCUGUUUAGGACACCACAGAGUGCCACUGAAAACCCAAAGCAAGAUGCAAAUGGACACAUUUUUUUUCUGAAGACUUAAAAGUGCUAUGUGAACAUAAGAUAAACUGUUAUGAUUACCCUGCUGUCAGAAGUUAUUUUAAUCCUGUCAGGGUUGCUAAACUUUCUGAUCUGGAACCAAAAUUGCUCUUUAAACAGGAAGAGCAUUGGUGCUGGUAGGUCACCUACGCCUUUGCCCUCAUGGCUUCCCCUUGUCCCCCCUAGAGGCACAGGAGGCCACUCACUCUUGGAGGGCAUAGCUGGACCAGGAGCAUGAGCUGUGGCCCAGACUCAGGGAACCUCUGUGAGUCAGCUGGCAAAGGCUCCCGGGGAGCCUGUCUCUGAAUCUGGUCCUAGCCCGUUCACUUGGAAAAAACAGGAGACUUCUCCCAAGGUCAAGGAAUUCAGAUUUUGGUUUUGGUUUCCAACUUUUUGUAAUCCUCAACCUGGGAUUUACAGUGCAUGUCUCAAUUAUGUUUCAUUCAUUGCUUCACAAAGGGAAGGACAAGCACUGGUUCAUCUCUUUACACCUAUACAUUCCUAGCACAGAGUGAGUACUCACAAAAAACAUACGGAAUACAUAGAGGACACUUUAUCUGUUGACCCCAUUUCCAAAUUUUCAGUGUUGAGCCAUCUUCUGAUUUCUAAACUUCUUUAAAUCCCUCUAAUUUUAGGUUAUACUACAGUAGAAAUUUAAUUGUAGCUGAUAAUUAUUGAGCACUUACUAUGUGGUUGGCACUGCAUAAAAUGCUUUAGAAAAAUUCUUACAUCAAAUAUGUGGAGUAGGUACUAAUACUAUCCUAACAUUAAAGGGGGGGAAAUAAAGUUUAGUGUAAUUAAUUAAUUUAUUCAAGGUCGCCAAAUCAUUCAGUGGUAGAAACAUGAAUCAAGACCAGGCAGUCUGACUGUAAAUAAAUUCUGAGCCACUCUCUUGCAGAGGACCUCCUGAUAUUCAUCUCCUGAAUGGUUGGCAACAGGCCUGUUCAUAGUAGACACACAAUAAACUUUGACUAAAUGAACAAA